UGGGUGGAGGGGUUCAUAGUUCUCCCUGAGUGAGACUUGCCUGCUGCUCUGGCCCCUGGUCCUGUCCUGUUCUCCAGCAUGGUGUGUCUGAGGCUCCCUGGAGGCUCCUGCAUGGCAGUUCUGACAGUGACACUGAUGGUGCUGAGCUCCCCACUGGCUUUGGCUGGGGACACCAGACGAGGCCGCCUGUGUGACUGGAUCGUUCGUGUCCCCACAGCACGUUUCUUGGAGUACUCUACGUCUGAGUGUCAUUUCUUCAAUGGGACGGAGCGGGUGCGGUACCUGGACAGAUACUUCCAUAACCAGGAGGAGAACGUGCGCUUCGACAGCGACGUGGGGGAGUUCCGGGCGGUGACGGAGCUGGGGCGGCCUGAUGCCGAGUACUGGAACAGCCAGAAGGACCUCCUGGAGCAGAAGCGGGGCCGGGUGGACAACUACUGCAGACACAACUACGGGGUUGUGGAGAGCUUCACAGUGCAGCGGCGAGUCCAUCCUAAGGUGACUGUGUAUCCUUCAAAGACCCAGCCCCUGCAGCACCAUAACCUCCUGGUCUGUUCUGUGAGUGGUUUCUAUCCAGGCAGCAUUGAAGUCAGGUGGUUCCGGAAUGGCCAGGAAGAGAAGACUGGGGUGGUGUCCACAGGCCUGAUCCACAAUGGAGACUGGACCUUCCAGACCCUGGUGAUGCUGGAAACAGUUCCUCGGAGUGGAGAGGUUUACACCUGCCAAGUGGAGCACCCAAGCGUGACAAGCCCUCUCACAGUGGAAUGGAGAGCACGGUCUGAAUCUGCACAGAGCAAGAUGCUGAGUGGAGUCGGGGGCUUUGUGCUGGGCCUGCUCUUCCUUGGGGCCGGGCUGUUCAUCUACUUCAGGAAUCAGAAAGGACACUCUGGACUUCAGCCAAGAGGAUUCCUGAGCUGAAGUGCAGAUGACACAUUCAAAGAAGAACUUUCUGCCCCAGCUUUGCAGGAUGAAAAGCUUUCCCUCCUGGCUGUUAUUCUUCCACAAGAGAGGGCUUUCUCAGGACCUGGUUGCUACUGGUUCAGCAACUGCAGAAAAUGUCCUCCCUUGUGGCUUCCUCAGCUCCUGUUCUUGGCCUGAAGCCCCACAGCUUUGAUGGCAGUGCCUCAUCUUCAACUUUUGUGCUCCCCUUUGCCUAAACCCUAUGGCCUCCUGUGCAUCUGUACUCACCCUGUACCACAAACACAUUACAUUAUUAAAUGUUUCUCAAAGAUGGA